GGGGCUGGGGGCCAUGGGCGGGGGUCCCGCCAAAGUCAGGAAGCCAAGCAGAGCCACCUCCCGCGACCCUUCCCCUCCAUUCAGCUGGAGCCGGGUGCCCCUCAGGGCACCGGGCGGACAGGCCAAGGUACCCCACAGGAACCUUUUUCCUUCCUGAAGUGGCAGGAACCCCGCCCCUCCCAGAGCCGGUGGGGGUCGGCGUUGCAGGAAACCCAGGCCUGGGAGCCUCCUCUGCCCUCCUCCAAGGCCCCUGCAGGCUCUGUUCCCCCAAGGGACCCCAGGUCCAGGGCCUCCUGCCCACUGUGGCAGCUGGAAACUCAGAGCCCCGAGUCAGGACCCGGGUGAGAUGGCGCUAGAGCCCGGGAACGGGUGGAGUAGACGAGGUCGCGUCCCCUUGGCGGGCGCACGGCAGAAAGAACCCCUCGCCAGGGAGCGCGCAGCCUACCUGGUUCUUCGCGGCUGUGAGGAUUUACAAACCUUUUGGAAAGCAGUUUGGCAACACCUACUACCCUGCCCCUACUUCUGUGAAUAAAAGUGUAUUCCGCAGAAGUAAGAUCGAUUGGGGAGGGUUUUCUGUUGGGAAAAGCAGUCACUGGCAGCUGCCUGAAUGUCCUUAGAGUGGCCACGACCCAGCACAGGAUGCAGAGCUUCCUGACUCUGCUGAAGGAGCAUGAGGACACCUGUGCACCCCCGGCGGAGCUGGUGACCCUUGCGGGCAGACUGUGCCGGGACUUCCAGGAUGACCUUGCCCAACUGCAGCCUUUGGUCACAGCCAUUCUGGACAGCCAGCUCCGCCUGCAUCUCCUGGACAACGCAGAUGUGGCCCUGGCGUGCGCCCGUGUCCUGGACCAGCAGGAGCAGCAGCAGGCGGCUUGCCGCCUCCUGGAGGGGUGCCAGGUGCCGGGAGGCAGCCAGGAGUUAGUGCAGCUCUGGAACGACAUCCACUACCGUCUGGUCAUGAGGAGGCUGGGCGUGGCUGCGCUCACCCCGGUGCAGAAGUUCCGCUGCAGGAAGAGGAACCCCCCGCCCCCCUCCCUCUGCCCAGAGGGGCUGAAGAGCCGGAACUUCCCCAGAGAGGUUCGUGAGAAGCUGCACAAUUUCGCUGUGGGGGUGAACACCAACCCCAGCAAGGCUGAGAGGGAGAACUUGGCAUUGGAGACGAGCUUGACCCCUGAGCAGGUGUACAACUGGUUUGCCAAUUACCGGCGCCGCCAAAGAGCCCUUCCCCAGCACAUGAAGCCAGCCCAGCAGGCCACAGCUGAAGACCCUGGUGCGAGGGAGAGGGGUCCUGACCUCCUGCAGCCCUCAGGCAACCCCCGUGUUGACUCUGGGUUUGUGGACAGGCCUCAGUGGUCAGAGGAACGUGAGGAAAAGGGGCCUCCACAGUCCCCACAGACCACCCAAGGACCAUGGGAGCCACUGGCCUUAGCCCCGGACUUUCCCGCAGAUGAGACAGUCUCAAAGCCACUGGAUGUCAGGUCUCUGCCAGGUGGCGAGAUGUACCAGGAGGGGCCUGGCCAUGAUCCUGCCACCCUCCCCCUCUUCUGCCCUGGCCCUGGCCUCUGCCCUCUGGCUGCUGGCAAUGACAUGCUGAACCCCUCUCUGGCUGCCCCUGAAUCUUGGCUGAUGUCUCUUGCACUGGCGUCCUCCAAGGAAGUUUCCUUCCAGACUGGGCAGCUGGUCCACAGCCAUGGGCUGGACUUCAUGAUGGGCCCUGCAGACACCGCUGUGGCUGUGUCCAUUGCCACCCUUGGAGAUCCCAGCCCUACAGUGUGCCGUGGAAUCUCAUUACAUGCAGGGUUUUCUGGCCCCCCCAGCGGCCAUCCCCAGAGCGUGCAAUUGGAGGAGGGUCUGGGCACAAGCAGUGGACGGACAGAGCUACGGGUGGGCAGCUUCCUGGUGACACAGCCCCCACUGCAAGCUCCUGAAUUCAUCCUCACCCAGAGCCCUCCAGAGCUGGCCCCAGCCCCAUCUGCCUUCCCCGGCCCUGUGUCUGCCAUGGAGCUGAGCCAGGCCCUGCCCUCCAGCCAGGUGCAGUGUUCUGAUAGCCAGGCCUCUGGUGAUGCCUUCUGGGGAGCCAGGAUGCUCCUUGAGUUUUCAGGGAGCAGCCUGGGCUGAGCUAUCCCCAGGAGCCAGACAGCACCCCAGGAGGAGCGGGUGUGGAUGGUCUGCCUGGUCAACACAAGGAGUUACAGAGCUUUAUCCUGAAUACAAAAUGAAGGUCCCCAGAGUUCCCCUGGGGGCUCUGCUGAAAAGCAGAGAUUCUUUCCCACUGCCAUGUUUGAAUAGUUUGGUUAGCAAUUCCCUGUAGUAGAGAAAGCAUUUGAGAAAUGUUCGUGAGAUCAGAAGUCAAAGGUGGGUCUGUCCCACUCACGCAGCACUGGAUCAGUCGGGCUCCGGGGCACUCGUGCAGAGAAGGCCAUUCUAGAGAGGGGAGUGUUCUGCUGCUGGCUGCCUUGCCGUCUGCCCGUGCACACAGCCAGACUUUUCCACCAAGUUAACUGAGUGAGGUAUGAGGAGUGUUCUGAGAUUUCUGUGUGUAGGGGCUUCUCCCUUGAGUACUGGGAGGCAAACCUGUCUGCGAAUGGCCUAGGCAGGGCAGAGUAGGGUGGAUUUUCCCUCCAGGUUGUAAUUCACUGUGUCUAUGACACAAAUGUUGUAGUCAAUUAAAGUUUAAUGUUUUGAACUCCC